CUUCCUUAACACAACACAGUUCAACCCAUUAGGGAGCUGCCACCUGAAAUCGUGAAAAAUUAUCAAAACAGUAAGUAUUUUAAGCCUCUGGUAAACAUCCUUCUACUCUCUAUGUCUAUGAGUUCAACUGAUUUGAUUUUCAGAUGUCACGAAUAAGUGAGAACAUACGAUGUCUUUCUAAAGGACCUAAAGAUAUAUUGAAAAAGACGCAGCCUAGAAGACUAUAUUUAGUGGUGUUAAAUGUAGAUUUGCUUCUGGAGCUUGAAAGGAAAGGAAUCACAACUGAACAUCAAAUGAAAGCCUAUGAGAAUAUUCAUUUUGUAAAAACCUUGAACACAACUUUUUCUCACAUUAUAGAUAAAAUAAUUGUACAUCAACCCAUCUACAGGUACUAGAGGGUUGAGAAUAAGGAAUGCCAGCAGAGAAGAAUAAAAAGACCGGGGAAAGGCUCAGGGACAACGGUUGUAUUCUGUUGUCAUUGUUGUUUGUUUGUUUUUCAGGAAAAAUGUAAUUUAAUCUUAAUACAAUCCUCAGAUGAUAACAACUGAAGAGAAUUAAUGUUAUUAAUUACCUGGAUAUAUCCUAUAUUCAGAGUUUGUCCUGGACAAAAAAUGUUUAAGUACCUAUAAAAUGACAUCAUUUCUUUCUAACCCAUUUGUAAAUCCAUUCCAUGUAACAAACUACAAUCAACUGCAUUUGUAAAUUCUGAUGGAUAAGGAAUGAUCAAAGAAAAAGUUGGAUUGUUUUACAAAACUUGAUUUCUUAAGGAGAUAUCCACUGCUCAUAUAUGUGAAAUUUAGAAAGGUUAUUGGAACACUGGCAACAUUGAUUAUUCUAUAAAGGGAGAAAAUAAAAGUAGGCUGGUCAGCUUGGCUUCUAGAUGCAUAUCCUUUUGCUAUAGAAUUCAAAUAUCUACCCCCUCAUAAACCGUGAUUUUUAAAGGAGGAUUGGGUAGAUAUCAAAGAACAGUGAUGAAAAACCACACAGUAAUAAGAACUUUUAUCCUGCUGGGACUGACAGGUGACCCACACCUGCAAGUUCUGCUUUUUAUCUUUCUAUUUCUCACCUACAUGUUGAGUGUAACAGGGAACCUGACUAUUAUCACCCUCACAUUGGUGGACCACCACCUUAAAACUCCUAUGUACUUCUUUCUCAGAAAUUUUUCCUUCUUAGAAGUCUCAUUUACUACAGUCUGCAUUCCCAGAUUCUUGUACAAUAUAUCAAUGGGGGACAAUACCAUUACCUACAAUGCUUGUGCCAGUCAAAUAUUCUUUGUUAUUCUCUUUGGAGCAACAGAAUUUUUUCUCUUGGCAGCCAUGUCCUAUGACCGCUAUGUGGCCAUCUGUAAACCCCUUCAUUAUGUGGUCAUCAUGAACAACAGGGUGUGUACCUUAUUAGUUCUCUGCUGUUGGGUGGCUGGCUUGAUGAUCAUUGUUCCACCACUUAGCUUAGGCCUCCAGCUCGAAUUCUGUGACUCCAAUGCCAUUGAUCAUUUUAGCUGUGAUGCAGGUCCUCUCCUAAAGAUCUCAUGCUCAGAUACAUGGGUAAUAGAACAGAUGGUUAUACUUAUGGCUGUAUUUGCACUCAUUAUCACCCUAGUUUGUGUGAUUCUGUCCUACUUGUACAUAGUCAGAACAAUUCUGAAGUUCCCUUCUGUUCAGCAAAGGAAAAAGGCCUUUUCUACCUGUUCAUCCCACAUGAUUGUGGUUUCCAUUGCCUAUGGAAGCUGCAUCUUCAUCUAUAUCAAGCCCUCUGCAAAAGAUGAGGUGGCCAUAAAUAAAGGAGUUUCAGUUCUUACUACUUCUGUCGCACCCUUGUUGAACCCCUUCAUUUACACCUUGAGGAACAAGCAAGUGAAACAAGCUUUCAGUGACUCUAUAAAGAGGAUUGCAUUUCUCUCAAAGAAGUAGAAGCUGUGAUGAAUUGGCAUAAAGUGAAUGAAGAAGGCUCCCUAAAUGUCAUCCUACAGCUUUUAACUUAUUUCAUUGCUUCCUGACUACAGUUUAGUCAUGUGAACCUUCUCAAUGACAUUUAAUAUUGCAUCCUAAUCCCAUCUUUAUCAAAAUCCUUAUUAUUUCGAACCAAGGUCAUACAUUGUGUUUUCC